GUUGUCAACAGCCCAGAAAGAGAAAGACGGAGAGGCAGAGACCCAGGGGAGCCGAGGAGCGGAGACACGGACCCAGCAGGGUCACGCGGGAGGAGACUCGGGACACCCACUCGCUGGCUGCCACCGGGAGCAGAGGGGGGCUCGGCCGCCCCCUCCCACAUCAGUCUCCAGACCCUUGGGGCUUCAGAGGCCGCUCCUAGGCUCCUCGGAGGAGGCGCGGGUUUCUUCUUUUCCGGAGAGCAAACUUUCCUCGGAGAUGCCUGGCAGGAUGAGCCGCGGCCCCCGGAGAGGACGGGACAGCCUCUGAUCGCCGCCUGCGUGCCCCGCCACUGCCCAUGGCCAGGAGGCCCCAGGGAACGGACAGCCCGACCUCUUAGGCGCCGGGACCCUCAGGCUCAGAUCAGUGGCCGAGGCCCCAGAGUUUGCAAACUCAGCUCUGGAGUUCAGCAGCAACAGCAGCAGGAAAAACCUGCCCCUGCUCCCCCCUCCCGCCACCUCCCCUCUCCUCUUCUCCCCUCACCCAGCAGGCACCCCCGGUUCCCGCCAGGCCCUCCUGCCAUGUCGGACCCAGACGUCCCCAGGGGCUCGGAUGUCCCCGCCAUGUGGCCCCCUUGUUCCAGGGGUGCCUGAGCCCCUUCAAGGAGCCCCAACCCACCCCCAACCUUGGCCCAGCCCUGAGCCCCAGGGACCAUGAGCGGGGGCAAGAAGAAGAGUAGUUUCCAAAUCACCAGCGUCACCACGGACUAUGAGGGCCCUGGGAGCCCAGGGGCUUCGGAUCCCCCUACCCCACAGCCCCCAACCGGGCCCCCGCCCCGCCUGCCCAAUGGGGAGCCCAGCCCCGAUCCGGGGGGCAAGGGCACCCCCCGGAAUGGCUCCCCACCACCUGGGGCCCCUUCCUCCCGUUUCCGGGUGGUGAAGCUGCCCCACGGCCUGGGAGAGCCUUAUCGCCGCGGUCGCUGGACGUGUGUGGAUGUUUAUGAGCGAGACCUGGAGCCCCACAGCUUCGGCGGACUCCUGGAGGGAAUUCGAGGGGCCUCAGGGGGCGCCGGGGGCAGAUCUUUGGAUUCCAGGUUGGAGCUGGCCAGCCUCGGCCUGGGCGCCCCCACCCCACCGUCAGGCCUGUCUCAGGGCCCCACCUCCUGGCUCCGUCCACCCCCCACCUCUCCUGGACCUCAGGCCCGCUCCUUCACUGGGGGACUGGGCCAGCUGGUGGUGCCCAGCAAAGCCAAGGCAGAGAAACCCCCACUGUCGGCCUCCUCACCCCAGCAGCGCCCCCCAGAGCCUGAGACCGGUGAGAGUGCGGGCACAUCCCGGGCUGCCACGCCCCUGCCCUCUCUGAGGGUGGAAGCGGAGGCUGGGGGCUCAGGGGCCAGGACCCCUCCACUGUCCCGGAGGAAAGCUGUAGACAUGCGGCUGCGGAUGGAGUUGGGUGCUCCAGAAGAGAUGGGGCAGGUGCCCCCACUUGACUCUCGCCCCAGCUCCCCAGCCCUCUACUUCACCCACGAUGCCAGCCUGGUUCACAAAUCUCCAGACCCCUUCGGAGCAGUAGCAGCUCAGAAGUUCAGCCUGGCCCACUCCAUGUUGGCCAUCAGUGGUCACCUAGACAGCGACGAUGAUAGUGGCUCCGGAAGCCUGGUUGGCAUUGACAACAAAAUCGAGCAAGCCAUGGACUUGGUGAAGUCCCACCUCAUGUUUGCGGUCCGGGAGGAGGUGGAGGUGCUGAAGGAGCAGAUCCGGGAAUUGGCGGAGCGGAACGCUGCGCUGGAGCAGGAGAAUGGGCUGCUGCGCGCCCUGGCCAGCCCGGAGCAGCUGGCUCAGCUGCCCUCCUCGGGGGUCCCACGGCUUGGGCCCCCUGCGCCCAAUGGGCCCUCCGUCUGAGCCUCCCUUCCCUUACAAUGUGCCUUUGGGGCUGCCCGGCCUUGCGUCAGCCGCCUGCCCCCUCUUCCUAUGCAGCUUUAAUGUCCCCGUGUCCCCGGGGUGGGAGUUCAAGGCUCAGUAAUGGCCUGGUCCCCCGGCCCCUGCCCCAUCUCCUCAUCAUCCCCAGCCUUGAUGGAGGAGGGAGGGCUUCAGGACGGGGCGUCAGAGGGAGCCCCCUCUGGGAGGGAACCAACCCCCACCCUCCCUCCUGGGACCCCCCAGCAGUAGACGGCUUGGGGGAGUCGGAGGCUCCCCGGCAGACACCCCACCCCCAUCUUGUUCCCUUGAGGUGCCUCCUCUCCUCUGCCCAGGGGAGGGAGUGUGGACAGUAUCUGGAAGUUCUGGGAUUCAGGUUGUUAUUAAAAUAAUAAUAAUAAUUAAAAACUCUGAAGAAACUUGAA